UUUUUUUUUUUUUUUUUUUUUUUUUUUGACAAUGUCUCUCUGUGUCAUCCAGACUGGAGGGCAAUGGUAUGAUCACAGCUCACUGCAGCCUCAAGAGCUCACUGCAUCCCUUCUGGGCUCAAGGAAUUUUCCUGUCUUAGCCUCCUGGGUAGCUAGGACUACAAGCAGGAGCCAUCACAUCUGGCUAAAUUUAAAAAACACUUUUUUUGUAGAGAUGGGGUCUUGCUAUGCUGACCAAGCUAGUCUUGAACUCCUGGCCUUAAGUGACCUUCCCACUUUGGCCUCCCAAAGUGCUGGGAUUACAGGUGCAAUCUACUGUGCCUGGCCCCAAAUUCCCAGUCUUUAAUCUAUAUUCCUUUGGAGGUUAAGAUGUCUAGCUGGGAUCAUUUCCACCAAAAAGGUUUUAGUUGGGGGGAGAGGGCCGUAGAUGUUAAAUCCUGGUAUCCGAAGAAGACUCUGAAGGAGGGGUAAAAUGUAGCCUCAGGCUCCUAAUAGCACCCAUCUCAAAAGGGUUUCUAUGCCUCCUCUGCUCUUUUCUGGGAAGUAGGAACCUAAAACCACAUGUUCCACUUAACUUAGGGCACUAGUGUCCAGAAAAUUUGCCCAGACCCUCCUCCAGAUGAGGAGGAAAGCCAACUGUUUGCCUGCCCACAAGCAAUUCUAUGUGACUGCAAUUCUAUGUGACUACUCCCUCACCUCCCACAUCAUCAUCAUCUUUUUUCCAAUUUGCCAGUUUCUUUCUUCCCUUUUGGAGUGGACAGAAAUGAGGCACCCACCCAUGAGUAAAGCUCUUUCUUGUAAGAACAAUAACAAAUGGAAGAGAAGAAAAAAGAAAGAAAUGCAAAAGAAAAGCCCCAACUACCAUGAAUAAAUUGAGACAAAGAAAAUAUUCCCUCAAAUGCACCUUUCCCUGGACAUCUGCCACUCCAUUCUUGCAGAGACGAAGCUGCUGAGUCAUUUUGUUAUUUUUGCUAUUGGCUGAGGGAGGAAACAGGAGAUUUUACCUGUAAUGGCAUAAAUAUUGGCUUCUAGGAUAAGGCCAAAGUCAGACAAGGUUGGGACAAAAAUCAUUCUUAGUGAAGGGGAUUUGUUAAGCAGCCUAUUAGUGCCAUCUGCUGUACAAUUCUAGAAAGCUAACUCGGGGAAUUUGUCUGUUGUGCGUAUCCCAUGCGACAGACAGUGUGAAGGAUUGACAGAUAGAUAUGAAGCUGAAUACUACCAAGCACCAACUUCCUAGAGAUUUACAGGCUAGUGAAAGUGGAAGACAUUCCAACAGACAAGUUACAGUGUGUUUUGUGCAACGUAAGAUGGAAAGGCAGCAAAGAAGCAUCUUUAGGUUAACAAGGUACCCCAUAAGGAUUCUGAUGGGUCACUAGUUUACCAGGCAGAAGGGAGGCGGAUGCAAGGCACUGCCAGCAAAGGGAGGAGUGUGGGCAACACCCUCAAGCACAAAAUGACAUCUCAUUGGUAAACAGCUUAGUUUAUAUUCUGUAGGCAAUGAAGCCUCUGACUGGUUUUAGGCAAGGGUAUAAUUUGGUCAGACUGACAUUUUACAAAGAUAUUCUAGCUGCAAGCAAGCUGGGGAACGAAUUAGGACAGAUUGGAGGCAGAGAGAUUAACCAGUUACAAGUCUAUUGCAACAGACCAGUUAACAAAUGAUUCCAGUUAGAUCAAGGCAGAGGCUGUGAGAAAGGAAAGGAAGGGAUGAAUCUGAGAGAUAUUUCAAAGUAAAAUGGACAAUAGUGAUAUUUCAUUGUCUAAGGGACAGAGAGAUGUUUCAUAAGCCAAGGGAAAGAGAAAGGCUUUGGUUUGAGUGCCUGGGUGGAGGAGGGGGUGCAAGUGAAGCAUUUGUUUGGGACAAGUUGAAUUUGAAGUGCUAUAGUCUAUCCAUAAGAUAAAUGAACAGAUGGGUCUAAAGUUCAGUGAUCAUCUCAUCCUAUCUCUUCAUUUCCCAAGGUGGGAAUUUACUUUUUUAAAAUUAUUUUUAUUAAAACAAUUUUUUUCUCCUCCCUUCUCUACCAAGACCACGGUGAAAAUUUUCUAUUAGAGCAAGAUAUUGCUCCUACCAUAGGUACCUCUGCAGCUCACAUUCCCUCCAAUUUAGAGUUUAUAGAAACCUAUUCACCAAAAUGGCAUCCUGGUUAUAUGAAUGUCUUUGUGAAGCUGAACUUGCACAGUAUUAUUCUCAUUUCACUGCCCUUGGCCUUCAGAAAAUAGAUGAAUUAGCCAAGAUUACAAUGAAGGACUACUCCAAAUUAGGAGUCCAUGACAUGAACGACCGCAAACGUCUCUUCCAACUUAUCAAAAUUAUUAAGAUUAUGCAAGAAGAAGAUAAAGCAGUCAGUAUCCCAGAGCGUCAUCUUCAGACAAGCAGCCUGCGCAUCAAAUCUCAGGAAUUAAGAUCUGGCCCUCGCAGACAGCUGAAUUUUGAUUCUCCUGCUGACAAUAAAGACAGAAAUGCCAGCAAUGAUGGGUUUGAAAUGUGCAGUUUAUCAGAUUUCUCUGCAAAUGAACAGAAGUCCACUUACCUAAAAGUGCUAGAACACAUGCUACCAGAUGAUUCCCAGUACCAUACAAAAACAGGAAUUCUGAAUGCCACAGCUGGUGAUUCCUAUGUGCAAACAGAAAUCAGCACUUCACUCUUUUCACCAAAUUACCUUUCUGCAAUACUGGGGGAUUGUGAUAUUCCCAUUAUUCAAAGAAUCUCUCAUGUUUCAGGGUAUAACUAUGGAAUCCCUCAUUCUUGUAUCAGACAGAACACUUCAGAGAAACAGAAUCCUUGGACUGAGAUGGAGAAAAUCAGAGUUUGUGUUCGAAAACGCCCCCUGGGCAUGAGGGAGGUACGUCGUGGAGAAAUUAAUAUUAUUACUGUAGAAGACAAAGAAACUCUACUUGUGCAUGAGAAGAAAGAAGCAGUUGACCUCACUCAAUAUAUUCUGCAGCAUGUUUUUUAUUUUGAUGAAGUCUUUGGUGAGGCGUGCACCAAUCAGGAUGUAUACAUGAAGACUACUCACCCACUUAUUCAGCAUAUUUUCAAUGGAGGCAAUGCCACUUGCUUUGCUUAUGGACAGACAGGUGCUGGAAAGACCUACACCAUGAUAGGAACUCAUGAGAACCCAGGAUUGUAUGCUCUAGCUGCCAAAGAUAUCUUCAGGCAACUAGAAGUGUCCCAGCCAAGAAAGCACCUCUUUGUGUGGAUCAGCUUCUAUGAAAUUUACUGUGGACAGCUUUAUGACCUCCUAAAUAGAAGAAAAAGGCUCUUUGCAAGAGAAGAUAGCAAGCACAUGGUGCAGAUAGUGGGACUGCAAGAGCUUCAGGUGGACAGUGUGGAGCUCCUCUUAGAGGUGAUCUUAAAGGGCAGCAAGGAGCGCAGCACUGGGGCCACUGGAGUUAAUGCAGACUCCUCCCGCUCCCAUGCCGUCAUCCAAAUUCAGAUCAAAGAUUCAGCCAAGAGGACAUUUGGCAGGAUCUCUUUUAUUGACUUGGCUGGCAGUGAAAGAGCAGCAGAUGCAAGGGACUCAGAUAGACAGACAAAGAUGGAAGGUGCAGAAAUAAAUCAGAGUCUACUGGCUCUGAAGGAAUGUAUCCGAGCACUGGAUCAGGAACACACCCAUACUCCCUUCAGGCAAAGCAAACUAACUCAGGUCCUGAAGGACUCUUUCAUCGGCAAUGCCAAAACCUGCAUGAUCGCCAACAUCUCACCAAGCCACGUGGCCACUGAACACACUCUCAACACCUUGCGCUAUGCUGACCGGGUCAAAGAACUAAAGAAAGGCAUUAAGUGUUGCACUUCAGUUACCAGUCGAAAUCGGACAUCUGGAAACUCCUCUCCAAAACGAAUUCAGAGCUCCCCUGGGGCUUUGUCAGAGGACAAAUGUUCUCCCAAAAAAGUCAAGCUGGGAUUUCAGCAGUCACUCACAGUGGCAGCCCCUGGUUCCACGAGAGGGAAGGUCCAUCCUCUGACCAGCCACCCACCCAACAUUCCUUUUACUUCUGCACCUAAGGUCUCUGGUAAAAGGGGUGGCUCCAGAGGGAGUCCUUCACAAGAGUGGGUCAUUCAUGCUAGCCCUGUGAAAGGAACUGUGCGCUCUGGACAUGUGGCCAAAAAAAAGCCAGAAGAGUCAGCACCAUUGUGCUCUGAGAAAAAUCGAAUGGGCAACAAAACUGUCCUUGGGUGGGAAAGCAGGGCCUCAGGCCCAGGAGAAGGCCUAGUGCGUGGUAAGCUGUCCACCAAGUGCAAGAAAGUGCAGACAGUGCAGCCAGUACAGAAGCAGCUUGUGUCUCGAGUUGAGCUCUCCUUUGGCAACGCCCACCACAGGGCUGAGUACAGUCAAGACAGCCAGAGGGGCACGCCUGCUAGGCCUGCCUCUGAAGCUUGGACAAACAUCCCGCCACAUCAGAAGGAGAGGGAGGAACAUCUGCGUUUCUAUCACCAGCAGUUCCAACAGCCACCUCUCCUCCAACAGAAGUUAAAAUACCAACCACUGAAAAGGUCUUUACGCCAGUACAGGCCCCCAGAGGGUCAGCUCACGAAUGAGACUCCGCCUCUGUUCCACUCUUACUCUGAAAACCAUGAUGGAGCCCAAGUAGAGGAACUUGAUGACAGUGAUUUCAGUGAAGAUUCUUUUUCACACAUCUCUAGUCAGAGGGCCACAAAGCAAAGGAACACCCUGGAGAAUAGCGAAGACUCAUUCUUCCUGCACCAGACGUGGGGACAGGGUCCUGAGAAGCAGGUGGCAGAAAGACAGCAGAGUCUGUUUUCUAGCCCCAGGACAGGUGACAAGAAAGAUCUAACUAAAAGCUGGGUGGACUCCAGGGACCCCAUAAACCACAGAAGAGCAGCACUCGAUCACAGCUGCAGCCCAAGUAAGGGGCCCGUGGACUGGAGCAGAGAGAACUCUACUUCCUCAGGGCCUUCUCCCAGAGACAGCCUGGCAGAGAAGCCAUACUGUUCACAGGUAGAUUUCAUAUAUAGACAGGAAAGAGGUGGAGGCUCUUCCUUUGAUCUCAGAAAGGAUGCCUCCCAAAGUGAGGUUUCUGGGGAGAAUGAGGGCAACUUGCCAUCCCCAGAGGAAGAUGGUUUCACUAUCUCAUUGUCCCACGUUGCAGUUCCUGGAUCCCCAGACCAAAGAGACACAGUCACCACACCUCUGAGAGAAGUCAGUGCAGACGGCCCAAUCCAGGUGACCAGCACUGUGAAAAACGGUCAUGCUGUCCCAGGAGAGGAUCCUAGGGGGCAGUUAGGCACGCAUGCUGAAUAUGCUUCUGGACUCAUGUCUCCCCUCACCAUGUCCCUCCUGGAGAACCCAGACAACGAAGGGUCUCCUCCCUCGGAGCAGCUGGUCCAGGAUGGGGCUACGCACAGUCUAGUGGCAGAGAGCACAGGGGGCCCAGUUGUGAGCCACACAGUGCCAUCUGGUGAUCAAGAGGCAGCCUUGCCAGUGUCUUCAGCAACUAGGCACCUGUGGCUGUCCUCAUCUCCCCCUGAUAAUAAGCCUGGUGGUGAUCUUCCAGCUCUGUCCCCAUCACCCAUCCGUCAGCACCCAGCUGACAAGCUGCCCAGCAGGGAGGCAGACCUAGGAGAGGCCUGCCAGAGCAGAGAGACUGUACUUUUCUCCCACGAACACAUGGGUAGUGAGCAGUAUGAUGCUGAUGCAGAGGAGACGGGGCUGGAUGGCUCCUGGGGUUUCCCAGGAAAGCCCUUCACCACCAUACAUAUGGGGGUACCCCAUUCUGGACCUACACUCACCCCACGAACAGGAAGUAGUGAUGUGGCUGACCAGCUCUGGGCCCAGGAGAGAAAACAUCCUACAAGGCUUGGUUGGCAGGAGUUUGGUUUGUCCACAGACCCCAUCAAGUUGCCCUGCAACAGUGAAAAUGUCACAUGGCUCAAACCCAGGCCGAUCUCAAGGUGCUUAGCAAGGCCAAGUUCUCCCUUGGUUCCCAGCUGCUCUCCCAAGACUGCAGGGACACUCCGUCAGCCCACCCUGGAGCAAGCGCAGCAGGUGGUCAUCCGAGCACACCAGGAACAGCUGGAUGAAAUGGCUGAGCUCGGCUUCAAGGAGGAGACGCUGAUGAGCCAGCUGGCUUCUAAUGAUUUUGAAGAUUUUGUGACCCAGCUGGAUGAAAUCAUGGUUCUGAAAUCCAAGUGUAUCCAGAGUCUGAGGAGCCAGCUGCAGCUCUAUCUCACCUGCCACGGGCCCACCGCAGCCCCUGAGGGAACAGUGCCGUCUUAGAGCCAGACCCUGUGCCGAGAUGGUGGGGGCCCUGCAGGAGUCUGUGCUGGGCUCUCAGGCUGGAGGAGCCUCUGCCAGGUCCUCCCUGCACACACCAGAACCCACACGCUGGUCCUGCCUAUGCUAGCGUCACCCCAGCCCCACGUGGCUUCAGAUAGGUCCCAGCUUCUCCCUCAGGGACAGGCCCCUGUCCCUCAGUUCCAUGCACAGGAGUGCCUCCAAGGGUGGGCCAGGCCGAAGAACCUAAUGCCUUUCCCUUGUGCCUAGAGAAUAUGAUUAACUAACCCCUUGCCUGUGGGAAUAUAUUUGGGUCUAAUAACCCUGAAGUUUCUAAGUUUGGGGAUCAGAGGAUGGGGUGGUCAGUGGUAGCCUAGAGGUCAGAGGUCACAAGACAGAGAAGACAACAUGCUGAGACCAGAGGCUUCACCAGCUGAAUUCUGUGCCUAACUUAGAAGACUAAACACUGGCCCAAACUUAACCAUUGGUGCUAGGGGGACAGGGGUGGGGUGAGCUCUGCCCCAUCAGCCCUUGGAGAUUGAUUUGGGGAUUUAGAGGCGUUUUUGAAAAUGUAAAUAGCAUAAACCUUGACUUGAUGUGUCACUGACAGCAGCAGAUGUGAGACAGGCCUUAUAUUUACAGCUCCCUUCCCUUCCUGCAAUCCAGUGUUGAGGCAGAAGAGGGUGCCUGUGUCACACAUCAAUUUUUCUCCUGACUUUUGCUCGGGUGAAAGGCCUCUGUACAAUGCCCGAUACUCUCAUGCUUCCAUGGCAGCUCCUGGCUCCUAUCUGGGACACCUCACUACCCAGCCCCCUCAUGGAAUAGUCCAUCUCCUAGCCUGGCCUUCAUCCAGUUCACCCUGCCCAGCCACCCUGCCUCUCAGGGGUCUGUGUUGGGAACCUUGGCAGUUGAACAGAGUGCUCUGUUCAACAGUCUGAGGCCUCUGAAACAGAAUUCACACACAAACCUUCAGCCAAGUUCUGCCUGCUGUGUAUCUUUUUAGCAGGAAGCAGCUCAGGACAGGGAAGACAAAGUAGCCUCCAGGUGCCAAUUACUUUAAAGCCACUCUGGGUCAAAUGGAGAUUCAUGAGUCACGGCCUUGGCCCGAACGCCCAUUACUAUGUGAGCCUUUAUUUCCUUCAGAUAAAGGAUAACUUUUUACGGUUUUAAAAGGAGGGCUUAAUUAAAAGGCCAAGAAGAGGGUUAAAUGGCUCUCUUGAGACACUAGCAGCCUGGUCCAGUCACCCUUUGUCAGCCUGACAGUGCCUCAUCUGACCGCCAGGGGGCAUCCUUAUUGGUGCUUCCCGGCUGCAGGGCACUGCGGCCCCUCCCUCACAUGAUCACUAAAAACCUUCAAAGACCCAGUCUAGCCAAAAGCUCAAGUGGGACAAUGGCACAGUAUUAAGGUCAAGGACAAAAACUUACUUACUUUAGGAAUGAACCCUAUUCUAUCAUCAUAUACAACAGCACCACUGAGAGCUGGUGAAACAGUUUAAAUCCCAUCCUCUGCUUGUGGCAAAUGAUGCAUAAAUGCCUGCUGCUCACAGUAAAAGGGCUUCUUCCUCUUUUACUGGGUGAUCCCCCUGAAGGCCCAGCCUAUCCCAACUCCACAGUCAGGAAGGCCUACGUCCUUGGUCCACAGACGGAGCUGGGCCAGGUUUAAAAGACUCAGUCUAGGCUUGCCUUUGCAAACCAAAAACGAGGACAGGUCUGAAGUGGGAAGAAAGCUCCGAAAUAGAAAACGGUUAGGUCCUAUUCUAUCCCCAGCAAAUCUAAGCAAGAAAUCUCUUUAUACACCACAUGGCCCCCCCACUCCCAUAAAACAGCCUUGGUAAUAAAGAAGUUAUCACACCAAGACAUACCUUUUAGAUUUUUAUUAGUAGUUCUCUCUGAAGAAUCAAAAUAGUUAGUUAGCAAAUUAUUUUAGAUUCAAGACUGUAUAUCCUUUGUAUUUAGAUCUUUAAUGAUGUACAACAUAAUACAAAACAAACCAGAGAGACUGA